CAUUUCACCAGCCCAGGCUGGCUUCUGCUGUUGACUGGCUGUGGCACCUCAAGCAGCCCCUUUCCCCUCUAGCCUCAGUUUAUCACCGCAAGAGCUACCAUUCAUCUAGCACAACCUGACCAUCCUCACACUGGUCAGUUCCAACCUUCCCAGGAAUCUUCUGUGGCCAUGUUCACUCCGGUUUUACAGGGUGCUCCUCCCAGCUCCUCUCAGCAGGGACCUUUGCCCAGGGAAUAGAAGCCUGACCUGUCUGGGCCUUAAUUUCCCAUCUGUGAAAUGGGAGAACUUUCAAAGAAGGAAUAUGGAGGCAGGUGUGAUAUUUAAAGCUGGACCCAGGCCCACCUUUCCCUGUGCUAGGAUUCCAGGACAGGUAAGGAGCCAAGGGUGGGGUGCCCAGCCCCAAAAGGAUAGCCCUGGAGCCUGCGCCAGGGGGUAAGAGGGGAGUCUUUGUGGCCUAAAGCAGCAUUUCCUCAAUGUCCCGUUUUUCUGCUACAUUUCCUGCCCUGGUUCAGAGGUACUUAGCCUCUUUACUUACUUGGAAGUGUGACUGCCACUCAGAUGCCCUGGUCAGCCCCUCCUAAGCAGUAAUAAUUAGAACUAGGGGACUUCCGAUGGGCUGCCAGGGAUGUUUUGCCCUUAUGCACUUAAAAUGAACCCGUAACUAUUAAAAUAAAUGUCGCUCCUCCCCACCCUGUCCCUCCUGCCCCAGCCCCUACUUUGAGAAACUCAGGUCAAGGCUAAAGUCCAAGGCCUGGUUCUUGUCAGUGCCUCAGUUUCCCCAUCUGUAAAGUGGGGCGAUCUUCCGCCGCUCAGGCCAGGUGGUGGUUAGGAUUAAACCCUGAAGUCGACCUGAGCAGCUUAGCAUGGCGCCUGGCCCAGAGCGGGCGCUCCACGCCCGCUGAUAUUAUUACCAAUCGUGAUUUCGGGAGAGGCGGAUCUGGGGCGUAGAAGGUGGGUGGGUUGGGGAGGGCAUUUUGGCCUGGGGGCGGAUGGGGCCCGCGGGGUGCGGCGCCCUGGCGGAGUGGGAGGCGGGGCUUCUGUGCCCGGUGUCCCCACCCCGCCCGGACCCCCAGCUCGGGCCGCCCCUGGGUCUCUCCCGGGUCACCGGCGGGGAAUCCGUCCCCGCGCGCUUCCUCCUUCCUCCUCCUCCCGGCUGCCUGCCGGGCCCCUCCUCCCAGCUCGCGCGCUCCCUCCCUCCUCUUCCCCUCCCCGGGCCGCCGCCGCCUCCUCCUCCUCCUCCUCCCUUUCUCUCUCGAUCUGUCUCUCCCGGCCCGGAAUCCAUUCCGGCCUGGGAGCCGGAGCGGCCAGGCCGCCGUCUGCCCGUCCCGCUGGACGUCCCGCGGUCCGCCCUCCCGUGCGUCCGUCUGCCGGUGAGCCCGCCCGCCCGCCGGCCCAGCCCCUGCGUCCUUCAGGUGGACUUAGGAGUGGACAGAGCCUGUGUGUGCCCCUGGGCAAGACCUCCUGAACUUCAUGGACUCUGUACAAUUUGGGGCAGUGGUUGCUGGGUCACCUGGGAACAGAGAACAGAAGCUCAGAGAAGUGAAGCAACUUGCCCAGCUAUGAGAGACAGAGCCAGGAUUUGAAACCAGAUGAGGACGCUGAGGCCCAGAGAGGGAAAGCCACUUGCCUAGGGACACACAGCGGGGAGAGGUGGAGCAGGGCCUCUAUUUCGAGACCCCUGACUCCACACCUGGUGUUUGUGCCAAGACCCCAGGCUGCCUCCCAGGUCCUCUGGGACAGCCCCUGCCUUCUACCAGAGUAUUCCUCUGACGCCCAGGCUGGAGUGCAGUGGCAGGAUCUGAGCUCACUGCAGCCUCUGCCUCCCCUGUUCAAGCGAUUCUCCUGCCUCACCCUCCGGAGUAGCUGGGACUACAGGCGCGUGCCACCAUGCCCGGCUAAUUUUUUUUUUUUUUUCAAGUAGAGCCCGGGUUUCCGCGUGUUGGCCCGGCAGGUCUCAAACUCCUGAUCUCAAGUGAUCCGCCCGCUUCGGCCUCCCAAAGUGCUGGGAUUACAGGCGUGAGCCACCGCGCCCGGCCCUGCUGCCUCUCCUUGGGCCUCGUUUUCCCUAUCUGUGGAAUGGGUGGGAGGGAGGCCGGCCAAGGGGCCCCGGCAGCCCUGCCUGUUCCAGUGUCUUCUCUCUCUCCUGCCAGGACCAUGGGUAGCAACAAGAGCAAGCCCAAGGAUGCCAGCCAGCGGCGCCGCAGCCUGGAGCCCGCCGAGAACGUGCACGGCGCUGGCGGGGGCGCUUUCCCCGCCUCGCAGACCCCCAGCAAGCCAGCCUCGGCCGACGGCCACCGCGGCCCCAGCGCGGCCUUCGCCCCCGCGGCCGCCGAGCCCAAGCUGUUCGGAGGCUUCAACUCCUCGGACACCGUCACCUCCCCGCAGAGGGCGGGCCCGCUGGCCGGUGGAGUGACCACCUUUGUGGCCCUCUAUGACUAUGAGUCUAGGACGGAGACAGACCUGUCCUUCAAGAAAGGCGAGCGGCUCCAGAUUGUCAACAACACAGAGGGAGACUGGUGGCUGGCCCACUCGCUCAGCACAGGACAGACAGGCUACAUCCCCAGCAACUACGUGGCGCCCUCCGACUCCAUCCAGGCUGAGGAGUGGUAUUUUGGCAAGAUCACCAGACGGGAGUCAGAGCGGUUACUGCUCAAUGCAGAGAACCCGAGAGGGACCUUCCUCGUGCGAGAAAGUGAGACCACGAAAGGUGCCUACUGCCUCUCAGUGUCUGACUUCGACAACGCCAAGGGCCUCAACGUGAAGCACUACAAGAUCCGCAAGCUGGACAGCGGCGGCUUCUACAUCACCUCCCGCACCCAGUUCAACAGCCUGCAGCAGCUGGUGGCCUACUACUCCAAACACGCCGAUGGCCUGUGCCACCGCCUCACCACCGUGUGCCCCACGUCCAAGCCGCAGACUCAGGGCCUGGCCAAGGAUGCCUGGGAGAUCCCUCGGGAGUCGCUGCGGCUGGAGGUCAAGCUGGGCCAGGGCUGCUUUGGCGAGGUGUGGAUGGGGACCUGGAACGGUACCACCAGGGUGGCCAUCAAAACCCUGAAGCCUGGCACGAUGUCUCCAGAGGCCUUCCUGCAGGAGGCCCAGGUCAUGAAGAAGCUGAGGCAUGAGAAGCUGGUGCAGUUGUAUGCUGUGGUUUCAGAGGAGCCCAUUUACAUCGUCACGGAGUACAUGAGCAAGGGGAGUUUGCUGGACUUUCUCAAGGGGGAGACAGGCAAGUACCUGCGGCUGCCUCAGCUGGUGGACAUGGCUGCUCAGAUCGCCUCAGGCAUGGCGUACGUGGAGCGGAUGAACUACGUCCACCGGGACCUUCGUGCAGCCAACAUCCUGGUGGGAGAGAACCUGGUGUGCAAAGUGGCGGACUUUGGGCUGGCUCGGCUCAUUGAAGACAAUGAGUACACGGCGCGGCAAGGUGCCAAAUUCCCCAUCAAGUGGACGGCUCCAGAAGCUGCCCUCUAUGGCCGCUUCACCAUCAAGUCGGACGUGUGGUCCUUCGGGAUCCUGCUGACUGAGCUCACCACAAAGGGACGGGUGCCCUACCCUGGGAUGGUGAACCGCGAGGUGCUGGACCAGGUGGAGCGGGGCUACCGGAUGCCCUGCCCGCCGGAGUGUCCCGAGUCCCUGCACGACCUCAUGUGCCAGUGCUGGCGGAAGGAGCCUGAGGAGCGGCCCACCUUCGAGUACCUGCAGGCCUUCCUGGAGGACUACUUCACGUCCACCGAGCCCCAGUACCAGCCCGGGGAGAACCUCUAGGCACAGGCGGGCCCAGACCGGCUUCUCGGCUUGGAUCCUGGGCUGGGUGGCCCCUGUCUCGGGGCUUGCCCCACUCUGCCUGCCUGCUGUUGGUCCUCUCUCUGUGGGGCUGAAUUGCCAGGGGCGAGGCCCUUCCUCUUUGGUGGCAUGGAAGGGGCUUCUGGACCUAGGGUGGCCUGAGAGGGCGGUGGGUAUGCGAGACCAGCACGGUGACUCUGUCCAGCUCCCGCUGUGGCCGCACGCCUCUCCCUGCACUCCCUCCUGGAGCUCUGUGGGUCUCUGGAAGAGGAACCAGGAGAAGGGCUGGGGCCGGGGCUGAGGGUGCCCUUUUCCAGCCUCAGCCUACUCCGCUCACUGAACUCCUUCCCCACUUCUGUGCCACCCCCGGUCUAUGUCGAGAGCUGGCCAAAGAGCCUUUCCAAAGAGGAGCGAUGGGCCCCUGGCCCCGCCUGCCUGCCACCCUGCCCCUUGCCAUCCAUUCUGGAAACACCUGUAGGCAGAGGCUGCCGAGACAGACCCUCUGCCGCUGCUUCCAGGCUGGGCAGCACAAGGCCUUGCCUGGCCUGAUGAUGGUGGGUGGGUGGGAUGAGUACCCCCUCAAACCCUGCCCUCCUUAGACCUGAGGGACCCUUCGAGAUCAUCACUUCCUUGCCCCCAUUUCACCCAUGGGGAGACAGUUGAGAGCGGGGAUGUGACAUGCCCAAGGCCACGGAGCAGUUCAGAGUGGAGGCGGGCUUGGAACCCGGUGCUCCCUCUGUCAUCCUCAGGAACCAACAAUUCGUCGGAGGCAUCAUGGAAAGACUGGGACAGCCCAGGAAACAAGGGGUCUGAGGAUGCAUUCGAGAUGGCAGAUUCCCACUGCCGCUGCCCGCUCAGCCCAGCUGUUGGGAACAGCAUGGAGGCAGAUGUGGGGCUGAGCUGGGGAAUCAGGGUAAAAGGUGCAGGUGUGGAGAGAGAGGCUUCAAUCGGCUUGUGGGUGAUGUUUGACCUUCAGAGCCAGCCGGCUAUGAAAGGGAGCGAGCCCCUCGGCUCUGGAGGCAAUCAAGCAGACAUAGAAGAGCCAAGAGUCCAGGAGGCCCUGGUCCUGGCCUCCUUCCCCGUACUUUGUCCCGUGGCAUUUCAAUUCCUGGCCCUGUUCUCCUCCCCAAGUCGGCACCCUUUAACUCAUGAGGAGGGAAAAGAGUGCCUAAGCGGGGGUGAAAGAGGACGUGUUACCCACUGCCAUGCACCAGGACUGGCUGUGUAACCUUGGGUGGCCCCUGCUGUCUCUCUGGGCUGCAGAGUCUGCCCCACAUGUGGCCAUGGCCUCUGCAACUGCUCAGCUCUGGUCCAGGCCCUGUGGCAGGACACACAUGGUGAGCCUAGCCCUGGGACAUCAGGAGACUGGGCUCUGGCUCUGUUCGGCCUUUGGGUGUGUGGUGGAUUCUCCCUGGGCCUCAGUGUGCCCAUCUGUAAAGGGGCAGCUGACAGUUUGUGGCAUCUUGCCAAGGGUCCCUGUGUGUGUGUAUGUGUGUGCAUGUGUGCGUGUCUCCAUGUGCGUCCAUAUUUAACAUGUAAAAAUGUCCCCCCCGCUCCGUCCCCCAAACAUGUUGUACAUUUCACCAUGGCCCCCUCAUCAUAGCAAUAACAUUCCCACUGCCAGGGGUUCUUGAGCCAGCCAGGCCCUGCCAGUGGGGAAGGAGGCCAAGCAGUGCCUGCCUAUGAAAUUUCAACUUUUCCUUUCAUACGUCUUUAUUACCCAAGUCUUCUCCCGUCCAUUCCAGUCAAAUCUGGGCUCACUCACCCCAGCGAGCUCUCAAAUCCCUCUCCAACUGCCUAAGGCCCUUUGUGUAAGGUGUCUUAAUACUGUCCUUUUUUUUUUUUUAACAGUGUUUUGUAGAUUUCAGAUGACUAUGCAGAGGCCUGGGGGACCCCUGGCUCUGGGCCGGGCCUGGGGCUCCGAAAUUCCAAGGCCCAGACUUGCGGGGGGUGGGGGGGUAUCCAGAAUUGGUUGUAAAUACUUUGCAUAUUGUCUGAUUAAACACAAACAGACCUCAGAAUCUGAUCAACAGUUUAUUGAACAUCUACUGUGUGCUGGAAAGCGAGAUGGGGCGGAAUGCGAGAACAAACUACCCCUUGAGGGGUCUUUGGGCAGCACUAGUAGCUGGAGGGCUUCAGGCCAAGGCAGGGGUGACAUCAGAUUGGAGACAGCUACGGCAGAAUGUGGCUGUUUGUGAACAUCUGCACCUGUGUUAGGGGGUGAGCACCUGGGAGAAGGACAAGGCACAUCACAGGACUUCCCUGAGCAUGACAAGUUCAGGACUCAAAUGUCCGUGGUGGAUGGUAGCAGUGACAUUGGGGAGUGGGUGGGGCUGUCAAGCCUGCCUAGAGGAGAUCACAAAUACACGACGAGAAUACCGUUGUGUGUGCUCUUCGUGUGUUUCCUAGGAGUGCAGGGCAGGGGUGCUGGGUCGAUCCACAAAAGUCCUGAAAACGCUGAAGAAAAAUCCAAAGACCCUUCCCCUCCUCCCUCCUUCCCCACCACCGAAGCACACAGUCUUGAAGGUUGAUUUGCAACCGUCUAUACAAACACAUUUAUUUUACACAAAUAUACAUCAGAUCACACACCUGUGCACCGGAGUCAACUCUGGCCACGACAUUGCUUAAUUAAAAACAAAUUUCAAAAACUGGA